AUUCCCCUAGGGUGCCAGUCAGCAGGCGGUUGGGGCGGGCCCGCUGCGGGGCUGGGGCGGGUGCUUUCUCGUUUAACACGAACCAGACAGGCAGUUAGGUUUGAACAAAUGAGGAUCCGGAGGUCCAGAGAGUAUAGGUGCAGAGAGUAAAGUGACAGGUCUAAGUAGUGAAGUAGCCGGGGCUGGAACCCUCGUCCCAGGCAGUGGGGCACAGGCUGUCUUCAUCGCGGAGAUGGCAGUCGGGGAGCGUCGCUCCAGAAAGGGCCAGGGAGUGCGGGAGCGUCCGUGUGCGAAAGAGAACGCCCCAGUGGGAUGCUUUGGCUGUGUCUCUCCCUUUUGGAGGAGUUGGUGGGUGGUGGAGUCGUUAAGUCCCGUGCAGUUGUUAGUGCAGGGUAAGAAUGGGCUCCUCCAGAGAGGGUAGCGCCGAAUAGGAUUUCGUUUGGAGGCAGGACUGGUGCCUCAAGGUCUCUUUAAAAGGAAGAUAAGCGAGCGGCCUGAAACUACCGGGUACUCCCUCUGGGCCCAUGGGCUUCAUGGUGGCCGACCUUUGGGUGAGAAGGUUUUUGUUUUUUGGUUUUGUAUCCGAAAUUACAUCUAGGGCUAAUGUUUCUUGAAAAUGUUAAGGUUGAACUCGGAUUUUUGGGGUUGAGUUGGAUGGAGCUUGCAUCCUUACAUUCAACUCAGAACAAGCUUGAAUGCCUGCUGCAAGGAUGACCUGGUCUGUAGUGUGACCACAAGAUAUAACCUUCUGCUAGGGGAAAUUUUUUUCCCCCUGGAGUUAGCUGAUCCUUUUUGAUUUUUAUGUUUUCAUUCCCUAAUUUGCAAUCUCUCCAGCCGUGCUGAUGUGUAUUUCAGGGGAAACCUGUGGGCCGAUGAGUUAAUGCAUUUAUUCUUUGCUACUACUAUUCUCCUUUUUAUGUUUUUGGGCUAAACCUGAAACAGCCAAUAUUUCAUGGAGUGAGGCCCCAUCUUUUUUAUAGCUUUACUUGUGAUACUAUAUCUAGGGUAAGAGCUUACCGAAAAAUGGAAGUCUUUGUUUCCAUUAGGUUUAUUAAGCCCAGUUUAAAAUUACUAAGAUGAGAAGAAUCAUUUCGUAAUUCAAAGUAGGAAACUCCUACCUAAUCUGAUAGAAUAUACAAUUAUUAGUAUCCCUAUAUAGUUCAUUACUCCUCAUAGGAACUCACUAAAUAAUGAAAAUUCUUGCAACAUUAUAUUUGCAUACCACUUUAAACUUCUUUGUGGAGUCCUUGGUUCCUAGCCCAGGUUGUGCCAGUAAGUGUUUAGAGUGCUGUCAUUUAAUCUUCAUGUCAGAGAGGGAAAGCGGUAUGGUACAGUAAGUAGUUAAGAAUGUAGGGCCGGGCACGGUGGCUCACGCCUGUAAUCCCAGCACUUCGGGCUUCCGAGGCGGGCGGAUCACGAGGUCAGGAGAUCAAGACUAUCCUGGCUAACACGGUGAAACCCCGUCUCUACUAAAAAUACAAAAAAUUAGCCAGUCUUGGUAGCACGCGCCUGUAGUCCCAGCUACUCGGGAGGCUGAGGCAGGAGAAUCGCUUGAACCCGGGAGGCGGAGGUUGCAGUGAGCCGGGAUCACACCACUGCACUCCAGCCUGGGCGACAGAGUGAGACUCCGUUCAAAACACAAACAAACAAAAAAACCCAAAAACCAAACCAAAGCGAAACAAAACAAAAAGAAUGUAGACUAAAGAGAAGAUUGCCAAGAGUGUCUUCUGGGUUCUGCCACUUCACUGUGUGGCCUUGGCAACCUCCCGACUUCUAGUAAAUUACCCAGAGCCCUAUCGUUCUCAGAUAUUGGAUUAUCUCUUUAAGCCGAAUUUUGGUGCCUCUUUGCAUAUUUUAAAAGUGGAAAUAGGUGGUGAUGGGCAGACAACAGACGGCACUGAGCCCUCCCACAUGCAUUAUGCACUAGAUGAGAAUUAUUUCCGAGGAUACGAGUGGUGGUUGAUGAAAGAAGCUAAGAAGAGGAAUCCCAAUAUUACACUCAUUGGGUUGCCAUGGUCAUUCCCUGGAUGGCUGGGAAAAGGUUUCGACUGGCCUUAUGUCAAUCUUCAGCUGACUGCCUAUUAUGUCGUGACCUGGAUUGUGGGCGCCAAGCGUUACCAUGAUUUGGACAUUGAUUAUAUUGGAAUUUGGAAUGAGAGGUCAUAUAAUGCCAAUUAUAUUAAGAUAUUAAGAAAAAUGCUGAAUUAUCAAGGUCUCCAGCGAGUGAAAAUCAUAGCAAGUGAUAAUCUCUGGGAGUCCAUCUCUGCAUCCAUGCUCCUUGAUGCCGAACUCUUCAAGGUGGUUGAUGUUAUAGGGGCUCAUUAUCCUGGAACCCAUUCAGCAAAAGAUGCAAAGUUGACUGGGAAGAAGCUUUGGUCUUCUGAAGACUUUAGCACUUUAAAUAGUGACAUGGGUGCAGGCUGCUGGGGUCGCAUUUUAAAUCAGAAUUAUAUCAAUGGCUAUAUGACUUCCACAAUCGCAUGGAAUUUAGUGGCUAGUUACUAUGAACAGUUGCCUUAUGGGAGAUGCGGGUUGAUGACGGCCCAGGAGCCAUGGAGUGGGCACUACGUGGUAGAAUCUCCUGUCUGGGUAUCAGCUCAUACCACUCAGUUUACUCAACCUGGCUGGUAUUACCUGAAGACAGUUGGCCAUUUAGAGAAAGGAGGAAGCUACGUAGCUCUGACUGAUGGCUUAGGGAACCUCACCAUCAUCAUUGAAACCAUGAGUCAUAAACAUUCUAAGUGCAUACGGCCAUUUCUUCCUUAUUUCAAUGUGUCACAACAAUUUGCCACCUUUGUUCUUAAGGGAUCUUUUAGUGAAAUACCAGAGCUACAGGUAUGGUAUACCAAACUUGGAAAAACAUCCGAAAGAUUUCUUUUUAAGCAGCUGGAUUCUCUAUGGCUCCUUGACAGCGAUGGCAGUUUCACACUGAGCCUGCAUGAAGAUGAGCUGUUCACACUCACCACUCUCACCACUGGUCGCAAAGGCAGCUACCCGCUUCCUCCAAAAUCCCAGCCCUUCCCAAGUACCUAUAAGGAUGAUUUCAAUGUUGAUUACCCAUUUUUUAGUGAAGCUCCAAACUUUGCUGAUCAAACUGGUGUAUUUGAAUAUUUUACAAAUAUUGAAGACCCUGGCGAGCAUCACUUCACGCUACGCCAAGUUCUCAACCAGAGACCCAUUACAUGGGCUGCCGAUGCAUCCAACACAAUCAGUAUUAUAGGAGACUACAACUGGACCAAUCUGACUAUAAAGUGUGAUGUAUACAUAGAGACCCCUGACACAGGAGGUGUGUUCAUUGCAGGAAGAGUAAAUAAAGGUGGUAUUUUGAUUAGAAGUGCCAGAGGAAUUUUCUUCUGGAUUUUUGCAAAUGGAUCUUACAGGGUUACAGGUGAUUUAGCUGGAUGGAUUAUAUAUGCUUUAGGACGUGUUGAAGUUACAGCAAAAAAAUGGUAUACACUCACGUUAACUAUUAAGGGUCAUUUCACCUCUGGCAUGCUGAAUGACAAGUCUCUGUGGACAGACAUCCCUGUGAAUUUUCCAAAGAAUGGCUGGGCUGCAAUUGGAACUCACUCCUUUGAAUUUGCACAGUUUGACAACUUUCUUGUGGAAGCCACACGCUAAUACUUAACAGGGCAUCAUAGAAUACUCUGGAUUUUCUUCCCUUCUUUUUGGUUUUGGUUCAGAGCCAAUUCUUGUUUCAUUGGAACAGUAUAUGAGGCUUUUGAGACUAAAAAUAAUGAAGAGUAAAAGGGGAGAGAAAUUUAUUUUUAAUUUACCCUGUGGAAGAUUUUAUUAGAAUUAAUUCCAAGGGGAAAACUGGUGAAUCUUUAACAUUACCUGGUGUGUUCCCUAACAUUCAAACUGUGCAUUGGCCAUACCCUUAGGAGUGGUUUGAGUAGUACAGACCUCGAAGCCUUGCUGCUAACACUGAGGUAGCUCUCUUCAUCUUAUUUGCAAGCGGUCCUGUAGAUGGCAGUAACUUGAUCAUCACUGAGAUGUAUUUAUGCAUGCUGACCGUGUGUCCAAGUGAGCCAGUGUCUUCAUCACAAGAUGAUGCUGCCAUAAUAGAAAGCUGAAGAACACUAGAAGUAGCUUUUUGAAAACCACUUCAACCUGUUAUGCUUUAUGCUCUAAAAAGUAUUUUUUUAUUUUCCUUUUUAAGAUGAUACUUUUGAAAUGCAGGAUAUGAUGAGUGGGAUGAUUUUAAAAAUGCCUCUUUAAUAAACUACCUCUAACACUAUUUCUGCAGUAAUAGAUAUUAGCAGAUUAAUUGGGUUAUUUGCAUUAUUUAAUUUUUUUGAUUCCAAGUUUUGGUCUUGUAACCACUAUAACUCUCUGUGAACGUUUUUCCAGGUGGCUGGAAGAAGGAAGAAAACCUGAUAUAGCCAAUGCUGUUGUAGUCGUUUCCUCAGCCUCAUCUCACUGUGCUGUGGUCUGUCCUCACAUGUGCACUGGUAACAGACUCACACAGCUGAUGAAUGCUUUUCUCUCCUUAUGUGUGGAAGGAGGGGAGCACUUAGACAUUUGCUAACUCCCAGAAUUGGAUCAUCUCCUAAGAUGUACUUACUUUUUAAAGUCCAAAUAUGUUUAUAUUUAAAUAUACGUGAGCGUGUUCAUCAUGUUGUAUGAUUUAUACUAAGCAUUAAUGUGGCUCUAUGUAGCAAAUCAGUUAUUCAUGUAGGUAAAGUAAAUCUAGAAUUAUUUAUAAGAAUUACUCAUUGAACUAAUUCUACUAUUUAGGAAUUUGUAAGAGUCUAACAUAGGCUUAGCUACAGUGAAGUUUUGCAUUGCUUUUGAAGACAAGAAGAUAAGUGCUAGAAUAAAUAAGAUUACAGAGAAAAUUUUUUGUUAAAACCAAGUGAUUUCCAGCUGAUGUAUCUAAUAUUUUUUAAAACGAACAUUAUAGAGGUGUAAUUUAUUUACAAUAAAAUGUUCCUACUUUAAAUAUACAAUUCAGUGAGUUUUGAUAAAUUGAUAUACCCAUGUAACCAACACUCCAGUCAAGCUUCAGAAUAUUUCCAUCACCCCAGAAGGUUCUCUUGUAUACCUGCUCAGUCAGUUCCUUUCACUCCCAAUUGUUGGCAGCCAUUGAUAGGAAUUCUAUCACUAUAGGUUAGUUUUCUUUGUUCCAGAACAUCAUGAAAGCGGCGUCAUGUACUGUGUAUUCUUAUGAAUGGUUUCUUUCCAUCAGCAUAAUGAUUUGAGAUUUGUCCAUGUUGUGUGAUUCAGUGGUUUGUUCCUUCUUAUUUCUGAAGAGUUUUCCAUUGUAUGAAUAUACCACAAUUUGUUUCCUCCCCACCAGUUUCUGAUACUACAAUUAAAACUGUCUACAUUUACAA